GCCCUGGUCCCGGAGUCGCCGCUGGGCCUGUCCGCUGGCGUCAUGGCACCGAAAAAGAAAGGGAAGAAAGGCAAAGCCAAAGGCACCCCGAUUGUCGAUGGGCUCGCUCCAGAGGACAUGAGCAAGGAGCAGCUGUUUAUUUUUAGGUGAAGUUGAGUCCUCCCUCUUUCUUCCUUGCCUUUCGCCGGCCACACGCCCCGUUGCCGUGCAUGGGCCCCUGCUCAGUGCCUCACCUGACCCACUGCACCUGGCCAGGUGGAGGAGCAUGUCAGCCGCAUCCGGGAGGAGCUGGACCGCGAGCGGGAGGAACGAAACUACUUCCAGCUGGAGCGGGACAAGAUCCACACCUUCUGGGAGAUCACACGGAGGCAGCUGGAGGAGAAGAAGGCUGAGCUGCGGAACAAAGACCGGGAGAUGGAAGAAGCCGAGGAGAGGCACCAGGUGGAGAUCAAGGUGUACAAGCAGAAAGUGAAGCACCUGCUAUAUGAGCACCAGAACAACCUGACAGAGAUGAAGGCUGAGGGCACUGUAGUCAUGAAGCUGGCACAGAAAGAGCACCGCAUACAGGAGAGUGUGCUGCGCAAGGACAUGCGGGCACUGAAGGUGGAGCUCAAGGAGCAGGAGCUGGCCAGUGAGGUGGUGGUGAAGAACCUGCGGCUGAAACACACCGAGGAGAUCACCAGGAUGCGGAAUGAUUUUGAGAGGCAAGUUCGAGAAAUUGAGGCCAAGUAUGAUAAGAAGAUGAAGAUGCUGAGGGACGAACUCGACUUGCGGAGAAAGACUGAGCUCCACGAAGUGGAGGAGAGGAAGAAUGGCCAGAUCCACACGCUGAUGCAGCGCCACGAGGAGGCCUUCACCGACAUUAAGAACUACUACAACGACAUCACCCUCAACAACCUGGCCCUCAUCAACUCCCUCAAGGAGCAGAUGGAGGACAUGCGGAAGAAGGAGGACCACCUGGAGAGGGAGAUGGCAGAGGUGUCUGGGCAGAACAAGCGCCUGGCAGACCCUCUCCAGAAGGCUCGGGAGGAGAUGAGCGAGAUGCAGAAACAGCUCGCAAACUACGAGAGGGACAAGCAGAUCCUGCUUUGCACAAAAGCCCGUUUGAAAGUCAGGGAGAAAGAGCUGAAAGACCUGCAGUGGGAGCAUGAAGUGUUAGAGCAGCGAUUCACCAAGGUGCAGCAGGAGCGGGACGAGCUCUAUCGGAAGUUCACCGCAGCCAUCCAGGAGGUGCAGCAGAAGACAGGGUUCAAGAACCUCGUGCUAGAACGCAAGCUGCAGGCUCUGAGCGCCGCUGUGGAGAAGAAGGAGGUGCAGUUCAACGAGGUCCUGGCUGCCUCUAACCUGGACCCUGCAGCCCUGACGCUGGUGUCCCGCAAGCUGGAGGAUGUUCUUGAGUCGAAGAACAGCACCAUCAAGGACCUGCAGUAUGAGCUGGCCCAGGUCUGUAAGGCCCAUAACGACCUGCUGCGCACGUAUGAGGCAAAGCUGCUGGCCUUCGGGAUCCCUCUGGACAACGUGGGCUUCAAGCCCUUGGAAACAGCUGUGAUCGGACAGACACUGGGCCAGGGCCCCGCGGGACUGGUGGGCACCCCGACGUAGCUGCCCCCCUGGGGGGCCACAGCCCAGAGAACCAGCCUAGGAACACUCGGGAUGACACCCCUUAUCACACCAAGGACAGCAAGUUUUUUAGAUUUUAUCAUCAGCAAAUGAAAGCUUUUCACAUGUUCUUGCCAUCCUCUUUCCUGGCUCUGUGGAGGAGAACCACCUGCAGGACCCUCACCCAUGGUGUCCCUGUCGCUCCCUUCCCUGGGUGCCGCACGUCCAGCCUGUGUCCAGGCCUACUCCCUGGUCUCACCUCCGACCACAGUCGGCGGCACCUUCUCAGAGUGCCCCGCACUCACCUGGGGGUUGGGGCAGUGCCGCGCUGUGCUGCCUGUCUUCGCGCCACUGUUGUCCCACCGAAUGGACAGCUUUGCAGGUGCUGGCACUAACUUCAUUGACACCUGAGUCACAGCUGCCCAGUGGGAUUCUCCAGGGGGCCGGGACUUCCCUAGGAAGUGGUGAGCCAAUGCUCCCUGAUGAGCACAAAGCCCGCUCUGUUGAGGGCUGGGUGGGUGCAGCCAGCGUGCGGGAACGGGCAGGCAGCCUCCCGCUGCCAGUCUUCGCUCUAACUCCCUCGGUAGGUGAUGUAGGACCAGGGGCACGUGGAACUUCUGGGCCUUGCUGGUGAUGGUUAAAACAACCUGAGAUGGAGAGGCCAGGAGAGAGUAUAAGGGGAUAGCAGCAAACCACCUAUCUGGCCCCAACACACCUGAGAGAAUUCAGCAGCCCAGACUGAGGGUCUGGGAUGGGGUGAACCUUCCGCACCAGAGGGACACUCCACAGAAGCCACAGCCCAGUAAGUCAGGCGCUUCUGCGGCGGCUCCAGUGUGGGGUGAGGCAGUGAGGUUAGGCCCAGAGAGCUGGAGUUGGCUCAGAUGAAAACCUCUGUCAACAAAGAGGGGAUGAAUCACCCUUGGCCCAGCCUCCCCACAAAGCCUGACCCUGGGCAGGUGAGUGACGGGUGUGUCCUCGUAGAGUCUAUUGCUGCCUGGACACCUUUCUUUUGGGAGCUCAAAGCAAGUGAGCUCACCUACCUGCCACCGCCCAGGACCAGUCUGCCCACUGCCUAAAUGAUGCCCGGCCAGCAGGACCUGGCCUGCAGAUCCCAGUGAGUCAUGAGCCUCAGCCCCCUCCAGCCCACUGGGGCUCUCACCUCCACAUGUGGGUAGAAGCUUUCCUGCCCCCUCUUCCUCCAGUAGCCCUCAGUGUCGAAGGUGAGCUUGUAGGUGCCUGCCUUCAUCUGGUCCAGGACAGUGACCAUCUGGGUCUGUGUAGCUGGGGAGAGGAUGAGGCUGCAGAGAUGGGGACCAGAAGCCCCCCACCCCAGCUUUCCUGGGUCUGCAUCCCAGUGGGCCUCAGACACUGCCCUGCCACCUGUCAGACUUGGGUGAGCAGACACAGUGAGGCUGUUAGGUCCUGCAGUUCCAGAGCAGUCUAGGGACACCACUGCCCUGUCUUUAGGAAAUCACAACACAGAGAAGCAAAAAGGGAAAAAGUCUCCCACAAUUUAUCCCAUGAGCAAGAACCACUUUAUAGCUGGCAUAUAUUUUUCCAGAUUUUCUCUAUGCAUAAGUAUAUUUGUUUAAAAACUUAUAAAGUGGAUUAUACUAUU